GGAUCUUCUUAAUCCAAAGGGCAUUUUCCUUACUCACUCCAGUCCCAUGCACUGGCCUUCAGGGACUGAGUAGAGUCUUGGCACUCACCUAGAAAACCCAUCACUCAGAAGUUUAUCAGCACAGACUCUGUAGGGAACAUUAUUUUGUGUUACUUCGUUGUAUUCUUAAAAACAGCCCCAUAUCAGUCUCUCAGAGUCUGAAUGGUAAUCUCUGCUCAAUAUCUCCAAUCACAGGUCAUGCUAUUGCAGCAUAUGAUUCAUUUUUAUAAUCUGGUCUUCUCUUUGCCCAAUUCCUGAAAGGAAACCAGGCGACAUCAUGGAAAGAAAGAAUCAAACAGCUAUAACUGAAUUCAUCAUCUUGGGAUUCUCCAACCUAAAUGAAUUGCAGUUUUUACUAUUCACCAUCUUCUUUCUGACUUAUUUCUGUACUUUGGGAGGAAAUAUAUUAAUUAUCUUGACGACUGUGACUGAUCCACACCUGCAUACACCUAUGUAUUAUUUUCUAGGGAACUUGGCCUUUAUUGACAUCUGCUACACCACCAGCAAUGUCCCCCAGAUGAUGGUGCACCUCCUCUCAAAGAAAAAAAGCAUUUCUUAUGUGGGGUGUGUGGUUCAACUUUUUGCAUUUGUUUUCUUUGUAGGAUCAGAGUGUCUCCUACUGGCAGCAAUGGCAUAUGAUCGUUACAUUGCAAUCUGCAAUCCUUUAAGGUAUUCAGUUAUUCUGAGCAAGGUUCUAUGCAAUCAAUUAGCAGCCUCAUGCUGGGCUGCUGGUUUCCUUAACUCAGUGGUGCAUACAGUGUUGACAUUCUGCCUGCCCUUCUGUGGCAACAAUCAGAUUAAUUACUUCUUCUGUGACAUCCCCCCUUUGCUGAUCUUGUCUUGUGGAAACACUUCUGUCAAUGAGUUGGCACUGCUAUCCACUGGGGUCUUCAUUGGUUGGACUCCUUUCCUUUGUAUCGUACUUUCCUACAUUUGCAUAAUCUCCACCAUCUUGAGGAUCCAGUCCUCAGAGGGAAGACGAAAAGCCUUCUCUACAUGUGCCUCCCACCUGGCCAUUGUCUUUCUCUUUUAUGGCAGCGCCAUCUUUACAUAUGUACGGCCCAUCUCAACUUACUCAUUAAAGAAAGAUAGGUUGGUUUCAGUGUUGUACAGUGUUGUUACCCCCAUGCUAAACCCUAUAAUUUACACAUUGAGGAAUAAGGACAUCAAAGAAGCUGUCAAAACUAUAGGGAGCAAGUGGCAGCCACCAAUUUCCUCUUUGGAUAGUAAACUCACUUAUUGAACCUCACAGGUUCAAUAAUCUUAUACUACAAAAUUAACUUUUUCACCAGUCAGCUGUUUUUAUUGAAAGUUUAAAAGAUAAUUGCAAUGUUGGGACAGAUAUUGAAGAGUUGAUACACUCCAGUCUAAGUGUACUUAUUCUUGAGCUUUAGUUAGUUCUAUGAGAGAUAUCAAUGUUGCUCUCUUUAGAUAUUAUCUUCUUAUUUAUUUUUCCAUUCCUGAAUUUUGCAUUCAAAGACUGUUUCCCUCUUUCAUGAGAUAUUUGUUUAAUGGACUUCAUCACUUGAAAAUUUCCCUGCUUUUUCAUAUUGCUUUCUGUAUAUUAAAUAAUGUGAAAUAUUUUUCUUCACAUUCCUCAUAUGUGUGUCAUAUUUUUCUGUUCUUACUACUUAAGCCAUGCUUUUGACCUUUCUUUCUUUAGUAGGCCCUUCUUAAUAAAACAUCAUCACCAAUAGAUUAAGAAAUGUAAACACAGUAAAGUGAUGUUUUACCUCCAGAUCUGUUGGUAGCUAAUUUUAAUUUUAUCACCUGCUGCAUGGGCCAAGGCCAAUUUAUCUUCACAUUGGAAUGAAGACAGUCAUAAUUUUCAAUCCCAUUUGACAUGCAUUCUUUAUUCUAUUCAAAAGGCAGAAUUUCCUGAGGGAUUUUUCUAAAACUAAGUCCCCAAAACAUAUUACUAUUUUAUAGAGUAUCUUAAAUUUGGGAAACUUUUUUCGCUAAAAAUUUAGAAAACAGAAUCAGAUAAAACAUACAGAAAAAACAAGGGUUUUUUGAUGGGGAAUAAAAAGUCUUAGUUAUAUAAUGACUAAAUUUAGAAAAAAAAGUAGAAAUUACUAAUGUUAAAAGUAAAAGUACUUAAUUACUAUUUUCUAUGUGUUAUUACCAUGUAAAGUACAGUUAUGAAGUCAAGACAAAUGGGAAGGAAGACUAAGUGGUGGAAGAGAGAAAUAAAUACAGACACUGGAGAGAAAAUUUAAAAGAUAAAGAGACUUAGAGAUACCAAGAAGGGAAAAUAAAUAACAUACAAUGUAAGAGCCUAAGAGAUUGAAAGAGAGAUAGAAAAAGGCUUAUAGAUCAGGUAGAUACAAGUUGUCUAGUGUCUUUCUUCACUAUUCUCUCAGGACCGUCUUCUUUUUCUUCCCAUACCUACUGAUGCCUCCCUUGAUUAAGUCUUGACUUCCCAGCCCCUCUUUUGUGUAAUGUUGUCAUAGUGUUCUAGUGGAGUGCCUUGUCUCCAUUCCUAUUCUGUUUAAUGUACCCUGCACAUCAUUUCUGAGUUAACUUUCUUAACAUGGUGUUAUGUACAGUCUCCUAUACUGUUUUUGUUUUAAUAAACUCUACUGGCUUACUGGCACACUCUUCAUUUAACUAAAUAUAUUUGUAACCACUGUCUAUAAAAUCUAAGUACUACCUACUUUGUAACUCAUCUCCUGCAGGAACCCUAAAUAAUUCUUCUCCAGGUAUGGCUUGAUCUUUCCUGAC